AACCUUCAAAAAGAAUGAAUAUGCCAUGAAUGGCUACCUGUAUUAUUGACAUUGCUGUGCUACUGUAUGUAUUUUUGUUUAGAAAGCACAACGUGUUUAAAGGAUAUCCACAAUUUCCUUCAAUAUAUGGAGGGCAUGCUGUGAGGACAUGGAAGAGGAAAAUGCAACAUUGCUGACAGAGUUUGUUCUCACAGGAUUUUUAUAUCAACCACAGUGGAAAAUACCCCUGUUCCUGGCAUUCUUGGUAAUAUAUCUCAUCACCAUCAUGGGGAAUCUUGGUCUGAUUGCUGUCAUCUGGAAAGACCCUCACCUUCAUAUCCCAAUGUACUUACUCCUUGGGAAUUUAGCUUUUGUGGAUGCUUGGAUAUCAUCCACAGUGACCCCAAAGAUGCUGAAUAACUUCUUAGCUAAGAGUAAGAUGAUAUCUCUCUCUGAAUGCAAGAUACAGUUUUUUUCGUUUGCAAUCAGUGUAACCACGGAAUGUUUUCUCUUGGCAACGAUGGCAUAUGAUCGCUAUGUAGCCAUAUGCAAACCUUUACUUUAUCCAGCCAUUAUGACCAAUGGACUGUGCAUCCGGCUAUUAAUCUUGUCAUAUGUAGGUGGUAUUCUUCAUGCUUUAAUCCAUGAAGGAUUUUUAUUCAGACUAACCUUCUGUAACUCCAACAUAGUACAUCACAUUUACUGUGACACUAUCCCAUUGUCUAAGAUUUCUUGUACUGAUUCUUCUAUUAAUUUUCUAAUGGUUUUUAUUUUCUCAGGUUCAAUUCAGGUAUUCAGCAUUGUGACUAUUCUUGUAUCUUAUACAUUUGUUCUCUUCGCAAUCUUAAAAAAGAAAUCUGAUAAAGGUGUAAGGAAAGCCUUUUCCACCUGUGGAGCCCAUCUCUUCUCUGUCUCUUUAUACUAUGGACCCCUUCUCUUCAUUUAUGUGGGCCCUGCAUCUCCGCAAGCAGAUGAUCAAGAUAUGGUGGAGCCUCUAUUCUACACUGUCAUCAUUCCUUUGUUAAAUCCUAUCAUCUACAGUCUGAGAAAUAAGCAAGUCACAGUUUCAUUCACAAAAAUGUUAAAAAAACAUGUUAAGGUUUCAUACUAAUAUCCUUUCUCUAAUUACAAAAAUAGUCACAAAAUUAUGCAAGUUAGAGGUACCUAUGUUGUUUCCAGUGUUCAAACAUUUUUGCAAGUACAACUGUUCUAGCACUUUAGUGAGCUAAUGUUUUAGUACCUAAUAAACUAAUCGCAAUAUGUCUAUAUGUUAUUCAAAAGCAUUCAAGAAAUUUUCAUACUGUUCAUAAUAGAAUAAUGACUGUAGAAAUCAAAUAAAACUAUUUAACAGUUGUAUAUGUUAUUCAAUGUGCAUUUAUAAAUGCAUUAAUUGCUAAAAUAGCCUAGUUUAUCAUAUAAGGACUUGAGUAUGAUGGUUUUGAUACUAAUACUACUGAAUUACCUGCGAUAUCCAUCAUAUACCAUAACUGAGGCAGAUUUGUUUUUGAGUGAACAGAGGUAAGUCCCAAUGAUUCUGCUAACCAUCAAGGUCUUCCAUUUCAUUAUAUUAGGAAAGGGUGAAUUCUGUUUCUUGAAGGAAGUCAACUCGCAGGUCAGACAGAAAUGGAAAUGCAAUGAGAAAAAUAAAAAUAGAAGGAAUGAACAGUGAAGGCACUGCCAUAGUGUAAGAGCAUGCUCUUAACUCUAUGUGCUCGUAUGAGUAAGAAGAGGCAAGCUGCCUCUCACUUUCUAGGAUGGCUUCUAAGGCCCUUCCCAGCUAUGAUUAUAUGAUUUUAGACAACCUGGAAGCCUUCCCUAAUUCAGGAAAUUAAAAGAUUAAAUAGAAUAACUGCAUUUGGAGUAGACAUAGAGAAGAAAUAAGUAUCAUAAAAGAAAGAAAGUGGUCUUAAUGUUUUUAUGAUGAAGCUACCAAGAUGUGUAAAAAUCAAUAAUAUUGCAAGGUUGUUGGAAUGUGUUGUUAUCAACAAGAAGUUUUAAAUGCCUGUCAUGUAAGUUCAAAUAAUGUUAACAUGAUACGACAUCAUGGUGCCCAGCAAGAGGAAGCAAAAACAAAAAAAUGAGGUAAGAUUUUGGAGAUUUUUUGCCUCGGAAAGUCAUUGAUUGUUAACCUUCUUAACACUUCUUGUACUUCAAGUAUGUUAAUCAUCUUUCUACCAGUCCACCCUCUCCUUCAUCUUUCAAUACUGAAAUUCCUUUCACAUUCUCACUGAUACUAUUGAGGUCCCUAGCAUAAAAACUACUCACAUGUAGUUUUGCAAACCUCUAGUUACUUAUUUCCUCCAUCCUUCUAACAGUCACUCACUUCCCCAAAAUGGCUGUUAGAUUGUUUUUUCAAAUGGAACUCUAACUAAUUAUAUCCCUCUUCAAUUCCUUUUGUUAGAUUGUCAUUGCUACCAGAUUAUAUGCAUGUAUGUUUUAGGUAUCUUAUAUCUAUAUGUAUACAUAUGCAUAUGUUUAGUUUUUCAUAUGUAUACAUAGUGAUACAAGAUAUAUAUUAGUACUUAUAUAGUUAAAAUACAAAUGUAGCAGCAUUAGAAUUUAGAGUUUAUCUGAGGAGACUCGAUUUAUUUUGCAACACCAGAUUGCAUGUGGUAUGGGGAUUUCCUGAAGGUGCAAGAGAGGAGAUAAAGGCUUUUACAGGGCAAAUGUGAAAGUAUGGCAAAAGUAAAGAUUGUAUUGGUUAAAGUGGAGCAGUAGUGUUAUUUUGAUCAUUCCAGUGGAAAAUUCCUAGUUAGAAAUUAGCUGGGGUUUUUGGUUGGUUAAAGUUAACUUUUGUUUUACCAUUUACAAUGAGUUGGAUUCCUGUUUGCUUAGGUACAAACCCACUUUGCUGGACCCACGUCAGCCUGAUAUACUUUUAUUUAAUUAUUUUAACUCAUUAUGGUCAGCCUCUCAUUAUGGGAUAUUGACUAAAACUCAGGCAUACUUGCACUCUCUGUGGCCAGCACAGCUGGUUUGUCUUUGUCUCAGCAUGGAACUCAUAAGUUACAAUGUCUGGUCUCUUACAGAAGUGUUUCUUUUAUGGACACUUCGUUUUUGUUAUUCUAAUCAUAGUGAGAAAAUCUGGCACAGUGUAGUGGCUACAAACUUGUAUUUAAAACUCUUGAGAGAAUACAACACACCAAGAAGAUGACAAUGACUAUCACAAACAUAGUACCAAGGGACUGGGGUAUGCUCCAUAGCCAAAGUACGUAUGAACAAAACCAACUGAAAUAAACCAAAUGAAAAUAAUAAAAGGUUAAUGGUUAAAACUACCUAUAAGCUUAGCAUGUGAGCCAGAGGGCAGUUAGUUGAGAAGACUUUUAGAUUUAAGCUCAAAGCAUCUUUAGAUGAUGAAAUAAAAUGGCAGUUGCAGUCUGAUAAUUUUUCUGUUUUUUAGUCUGAAUGUCUUUUGUCAUGUCAUUGAAUGUUUGGUGAACUUCCUGAGUGGGACACUAAGCAUCAUGCAUGAAGAUUAUCCUCUGACAUUUAUAUCAAGUUGUCCAGCCCUAGCUUGUAGCGCUUCAGGAAUAGGACAGUUUCUAAGUAGAUAAUAAAACAUCAAAGACAAUGGACAGAACUGGAAUUUAAUUAUGGGUGCGCUAUAUUUUUCUACUGAAACAUGAUUUUUCCCUCCAUAAUCAGGCCAUUUCUUUCAAAUGUAAUUAUAGUAAGACUAAUUUAUUUACCAACUAGAUCUACCCUCAUUAAGCUUCAAGUGAGUAUUUACAUAAGUGCAAGUUGGAAUAGGAAUUGAUCAUCUCUUUUUAAGAAGGCCUCAUUACGACCUUUACUAAAUAAUCUCCGAUUAGACUUUAAAGUUUCUUCAAGCUAUAAAGUCACACCAACAACAUACCAUUAGUUUCACCUGCAACACUGAUACAUUUAGGUAAACUCCCCUGUACUCAAAAAGGUCCUAAAAGUAUAUUUCAGUUCCUGGGCCUUCCAGAGAGUAAGGUCUUUCUUCCUCUUUACCAAUAUGGCUAGAAAGCUUGUGAGCAGCUAUCAGCCCAGAUUUUCUAAAGGAACUGGCUGUAGUUAUUUUUCUGAUACCUGCAAAUCUCAUAUUAAAAUUUGAUUCCAAAUUCUGGAGGUGUCGAAGAUGGGAGGUGUUUGGGUCAUGGGGGUCGAUCUCUCAUGAAUGCCUUGGUGCCAUCAUCAUAGUAAUAAGCAUGUUCUUACUGUCUUAGUUCCCAUGAGGGCUGGUUGAUAAAAGAGCCCAGCACUCCACUCUCUCUCUUUCCUUUCCUCUCUCACCACGUGAUCACCACACUUGCCAGCUCCACUUCGCCUGCUGUCAUGAGUGAAGUAGGCUGAAGCUGUCAUCAGAAGUGGACAUUUAAGCCUUGUUUUCUGUAUAGCCUGCAGAAUUGUUCUCCAAACAAACACCUUUUACUUAUAAAUUACCCAGCCUCAAGAAUUUCUUUAUUGCAACACUAAAUGGAAUGAGGCAGGGCUUAAUUGGAUGCAUAAAGUCAAUUCUUAGUUUCUUAAAAUUCUCCAGUCAUAUCUAAUUUUAUGCACAUUCUCCAAUGUGACAUUCCAGUCACAGUAGUGGUAAUAUAACCAUAAUUAUGUUAUAUUGUAAUAACAGAUUCUGAUUAAAAUUUUGCAAAUACCUAUAUUGCAAUCAAAAUAAAAAUGCUCAAUGAUGAUUUCUGAAUUCUGGAGAGGUCAGCUAAGGAGAAGAAGGUAAACGUAUUAAUUCUGUUUACAAAAGGUAUACUUGGCCAGAUUGUUUGCAAAGUUUCUUUAAUUCUGGUCUCGUGUUGUGUUUCUAACGUUAUCAGAAAUCUUUACUUGUCAGAGCCUUUUCCGCAAAUCUGUUGAGAUUAGACAGAUACUUUGCAUACAGGGAUGUUUCCUUUAUGUUAUUUAGUGGUAUUUAUUACCACACAUUAACUAGAAUUCUAAACUCUUAGUAACUUUCUUUUCUGGGAUAGAAGCGAUUGACAAAUAUACAUCACACCGGCAUUUUACAGAUUGGCAAAUCUACGAAUAUACAAUUUCAUAAUUCCUAGAAGUAUGUGCUUUCCCAUUAUAUAAUUUUUCAGUGUGCCACAGGACAUGUUGAACACAAAUAUGAACACAAAAGUGAACCCAAAUAUCUUUGUUUCUUCUGUAAUAAGAAGUCCAAAAUAGAGAAGUGUAUGUUCAGCAAUUAGUCUUUUAAAAAAAUGUUGUUUGGAAAUAAUCCAGAUAUUCAAUGACUAUUGAUAAUUUAAUCAACUGUGUGAAACUCUAAGGGUUUAAUUUACCACAGAGAAGUGGGAAGGUAUUUUUAAGUAGACUUCUUAUUAAACAUAAUUAUGGUUUAAAAGUUCAUUUAUAAACGUAUAUUGUACUUACAUCUAUUUAAUUCACUUAUUCUGAAUUGUUUGGUUUACUCAUGAAAAUUUCAUAAGACAUUAGACACAGCCAGUCAUCGUUUCAAAUUACUUUCUUGUUAACUACAUUUACAGCACGUUUAUGUCAGUGUAGCAGGACGAGCCGUGGGCAAAACCCCUCAGACACCGAGAUAGUGAAGGGAGUGGCUUUAAUCAGAUGGGAGCAUCGAUAGGCUAGCGUCUUAAAAUCCGAGCUCGUCAGGUGCUCAACUUCUGUCCCUUUUAAGGGCUCACAACUCUAAGGGGGUCCGCGUGAGAGGGUCGUGAUCGAUUGAGCAAGCCAGGGGGUACGUGACAGGGGCUGCGAGCACCGGUGGUCAGAGUGAAACAGAACAGAACGGGAGGUUUCACAAUGUCCUACCAUACGAUGUCUGGAAUCUAUAGAUAACAACAGUUGCUAGGUGAGGGGUCGAAUUUUAACAACCAGGCUUAGGUCAGGCAGGCCCAGGCCUGGUUUCGGGUCUGGUUCCUAGACGCCAGGCUACCUGCCUUUAGUUUCACUUCUCUUUCCUUUUCUGAGUAUAAAACAAUAUAAAACAAUAUGAGAGGGUCUCUCUCUUCCCUCAUCAGUCAGUCAUCAUAAAAGCAAAAAUCUAAAAGUCAAAUAUGUGUUUUUUUGUUUUAUUGCCGUGC